UGAUCCACCCACCUCGGCCUCCCAAAGUGCUGGGAUUACAGGUGUGAGCCACCGCACCUGGCCCAGCUGCUGUUACUCUGAAAUGAGGAGGGGGCAUUGGAGGGCUUUGAGCCGAGAAAUGUCUUGAUGUAAUACAUCAUUUAAGAGGACCACUCUGCCUGCUGACCAGAGUUGUACAAGGGGGAGCUGGAGAUGAAUUUGCAAUAAUCCAGGCAAGAGAAGGGGGUGCUCUCCCUGUGGUCAGGGUAGUGAAAGUGAUCAGAUUCCAAAUCUAUUUUGCAAGUAGGAUGAUAAGCUCUCCUGGCUGUGGAUGUGAGGAAGGGCGCAGUGGAGGCUAACUCCAUGGUGUCUGGCUGGGCAUCUGGAGGCUGGAGUUGUUAUGAAGUAAGAAGGGAAGACUUAGCACAGAGCUGGUUUGGGAGGCUAUGGCAAGGCCAUAGCUCUGUUUGGACACGUUUAGGUUUGAGGUGUCUAUGAGUCAUUAAACCAGUGGAGAUGCUGAGCGGGCAGUUGGAUUCAGAAGUCUGGGGGCUGGGACUGGUGCUAACUAGCACUGUGGUAACAGUUCCACUAUGGCCAGCAGGCACCGCCAAGCAAAGCCCUGAAGCUGUUUGUCCCAACCUUACCAGUGGCAGCGCAGAAGGCAGUCUUGGGGCUAGGAGCCCAGCUGGGAAAAGGUGUCCCUGCCCAGAGUGACUGCUUGGUGCUGGGGCGGGGCAUGGGGGCCGGAGACAGGCAGUAGGCCUGUGGUCAUCAUCGGAACUGCACUGCCCUGGCCUGGCUGUGUGGGAAUCUCACAGGCCUCUGGAGGCUUUUCUCAGACCCCCAGGAGUCAACUCUCCUGCCCUUGGGUUCCUCUGGAAUCAUGGGUGGAAAAAAGAAGGGAGAAAUACAGCUCCCUGAAGCCCUAGGGCAGGACAUGUGACAUGGAAAAAAAUCCAACCUUGGGACAACCUGGUGGGAUGAAAUGCAACCUUGUUAGCUGGUAGUGGUCAUCAUUUGAUGGAAUGACAUCUCUAAAAGGAAGCCCUGGAGGCAUAAUCAGAUUCAGAGUGAAAGGUGAUUACCCCCAGGCCAGGCUGCCAGUGGUAGAGCCCAAGGUCCUAGUGGACCACUUCUCCCCAGCACUGCUUGCUCUAUAUCCCAGCCCUCCUGGGAGAUUCAAGAAGACAGUCUUAUUUCUAGUUCCUGUGAAUGUCAACCUGCCUGGCCAGUGGGCCUGGGCUUUUCCAGGCAGCCCUUCCAAAAGGGGAGAGAAAGGACUCUUGCAGACCUGGGCUAGGCCUCAGGUCACUAAGCCAGCAGAAGGGGUACUUGAGACUAGUUCUGGUGCCUUCCAUCCAUUCUAGUGGGCCCUAAGGGUCCAUGUACUCAAGUGGAGAAGAUGUCCCUAUGGACCUUGGAUCCUGUCCAGGCUCAUAGAGGGCAGGCCUGGCCUCUUCUGGGUAUAGAGGGUGUUCAGAGCACACUUGGGCCUCCUUCCCCUGCAGCGCUCAAGGCUUCUCCCCUGCCAGAGCCCCAGGAGCCUGAGAACUUGGAUCCCCAAGGCAGAGGAAAUGGCCUCCAGCCACAGCCACCCUCCCCCACCCCUGCUGAUGGGACAGCCACAGAGCUGUUUACCAGAACAAAGGCCCGAGCAGCUGCCUUAUCUAGGGAGAGCCUGCUUGUUCCAAGUGGCCCUGGAGGACUUCAGCCCACACACCCUGAGAGAAGAGGAAGGGAGCUCACACUGGCUAUGGGCUGCCCUUGCCAGGAGUUUGGUACAAUCUGGAGGCAGCAGAGACUCAGAGGUUCAGCAACUUACCUAACAACACACAGUGGGGCUGGGGGCAGCGCAGCCCACCUCCAGGGGAUCUUUGGGCAGCGCCUAGAGGAAACAGUCCACCACGAGCGGAAGUAUGGCCCCCGCCUGGCGCCCCUGCUGGUGGAGCAGUGUGUGGACUUCAUCCGGGAGCGCGGGCUCACUGAGGAGGGGCUGUUCCGCAUGCCAGGCCAGGCCAACCUGGUGAGGGACCUGCAGGAUUCCUUCGACUGUGGGGAGAAGCCACUGUUUGACAGCACAACAGACGUGCACACGGUGGCCUCCCUGCUGAAGCUGUACCUGCGGGAGCUCCCCGAGCCCGUGGUCCCCUUCGCCAGGUACGAGGACUUCCUCAGCUGCGCCCAGCUGCUCACCAAGGACGAGGGGGAGGGCACUCUGGAGUUGGCUAAACAAGUGAGCAACCUUCCUCAGGCAAAUUACAACCUGCUCAGAUACAUCUGCAAGUUUCUGGAUGAAGUUCAGGCAUACUCAAAUGUCAACAAGAUGAGUGUCCAGAAUCUGGCAACCGUUUUUGGACCUAACAUUCUGCGGCCACAGGUAGAGGACCCAGUAACCAUCAUGGAAGGCACUUCCCUCGUCCAGCACCUGAUGACCGUCCUCAUCCGCAAACACAGCCAGCUCUUCACGGCACCGGUCCCGGAAGGGCCCACCUCCCCGCGCGGGGGCCUGCAAUGCGCAGUGGGGUGGGGCUCCGAGGAGGUCACCAGGGACAGCCAAGGAGAGCCCGGCGGCCCCGGCCUGCCCGCGCACAGGACCUCUUCCCUGGACGGGGCGGCCGUGGCGGUGCUCUCCAGAACAGCCCCCACGGGGCCGGGGAGCCGGUGCAGCCCUGGGAAGAAGGUGCAGACCCUGCCCAGUUGGAAGUCCUCCUUCCGGCAGCCGAGGUCCCUAUCGGGAAGCCCGAAGGGGGGCGGCUCAUCCCUGGAGGUGCCCAUCAUCUCCUCCGGCGGGAACUGGCUUAUGAACGGGCUGUCCUCCCUGCGCGGACACCGCCGGGCCUCGUCGGGAGACCGGCUCAAGGACUCGGGCUCCGUGCAGAGACUCUCCACCUACGACAAUGUGCCCGCGCCGGGCCUGGUCCCCGGCAUACCCAGCGUGGCCAGUAUGGCGUGGUCCGGGGCCUCGUCCAGCGAGUCGUCGGUGGGGGGCUCACUCAGCAGCUGCACGGCCUGCCGCGCCAGCGACUCGUCUGCCCGCAGUUCCCUGCACACCGACUGGGCCCUGGAGCCCUCCCCGCUCCCCAGCAGCAGCGAGGACCCCAAGUCCCUGGACCUGGACCACAGCAUGGACGAGGCGGGCGCGGGUGCCAGCAACAGCGAGCCCAGCGAGCCGGACAGCCCCACCCGGGAACACGCGCGCCGCUCCGAGGCCUUACAGGGGCUGGUCACUGAGCUCAGGGCCGAGCUGUGCCGCCAGCGGACUGAGUACGAGAGGAGUGUGAAAAGAAUCGAAGAAGGGAGUGCUGACCUGAGAAAACGAAUGUCCCGGUUAGAAGAAGAACUGGACCAGGAAAAGAAAAAAUACAUCAUGCUGGAAAUAAAGCUGCGGAACUCUGAACGGGCGCGGGAGGAUGCGGAGAGGAGGAACCAGCUGUUGCAGAGGGAAAUGGAGGAGUUUUUUUCGACCCUAGGAAGCUUGACUGUUGGGGCAAAAGGUGCCAGGGCCCCAAAGUAAAAGGAAUGGCAGAGCUCACUUCUGUACCACGUCUGCUGGUCUCCAGCCUUGUAUGGAGUUAGAAGCGUCUGUAUCUCUGGAGCAGCCAGGCGCUCUGGAGCCAGCUGGAGAGAGAGAGAUCCUGAUACCUCUGUGGGGACUGUGGGGACUUUUGGGACCCCACACACUCCAGGUGGGAUCAGAUGCUGCUCCAACCAUGCAGUUCCUGGUGAGGGUCAGAAGGGGACGGUACCAAGAGUAGCGCUUAGCCCUUACCCAGGAAAUAUCCUUCAUGGCCACAGAAAUGGAGGGCGCCCAGGAUCCAGGCAGCCACCGGGAACAGUCAGCUUUCUUUAUUAAAUGUGCUCACAAAGCA